AGUGUAGCCGGGUCAGCUGGACAGGGUCAUCCUGAGGGUGCGACUCCGCCGCGAUGGUGACCCGGUUCCUGGGCCCACGCUACCGGGAGCUGGUCAAGAACUGGGUCCCGACGGCCUACACAUGGGGCGCUGUGGGCGCCGUGGGGCUGGUGUGGGCCACCGAUUGGCGGCUGAUCCUGGACUGGGUACCUUACAUCAAUGGCAAGUUUAAGAAGGAUAAUUAAUUACACAAACCCUUCACAGACUGCUCUGGUGCCUGGUGGUGCUAGCUCCUCCCACCUCAGCACCUGCUGCAUCUGGAGCAGCCCAAGCCUCAGGAUGGACAAGAGGAAACCCACAGCUCAGCUUCAGGCUUCUUAUGUUUCUGAAAACAGCUUGGAUAUUUUAAUGCACGUUGCAUUAAACCUCACUGAAACCUGCUCCGUGCCCGGAUGUUGAUCAUGCUGGUGGCUUGGUUACUGUGACUGUAGCUGGAGUGGCACAGGUGACCCAGGCGUCCUUUCAGCUCCAGAAUGUUGCAAGUCUAGGAGAGUGUUCCAAUGGCUGACAGAAACUGCCUAUUUGAAAUGGCUCAUAAGUAGUAUCUGCAGUGUGUUCAUCCGUUGCUGCCUUAACAAGUCACCCACACGUAGUGGCUUAAAGCAACGAACAUUCACUCUCUCACAGUCUGUGUCAGUCGGGGAUUUGGGAGUGAUGUAUCUGGGUGGUUGUGGCCCAGAGUCUCUCAUGAGGUUGCAGUUAAGACAUCAGCCAAGGCCACUUCGUCUGAGGAAGGCUCAACUGGGGCUGGAGCCACUUCCAAGCCAGUGCCCUCACGUGGCUGUCGGUGACAGCCACAGUUCCUUCCCAUGGGGGCCCCUACACGAAGCUGCUUGAGCAUCCUCACGGCAUGGCCUCUGCCUUCCCCAGAGCAGGUGAACCAAGGGAGAGGAAGGAGCAAGCCACAGUGCUUCUAUGAGCCACCCUGAGAAGUCUCACGUGAUCACUUCCGCCACAGCCUGUUUAUCAAAAGCAAGCCCCCCAGGCCCAGCCCACGUGCAGAGGGAGGAGAAUGAGGUUCUGUGUUUUGAAGGGAAGAAUAUCAGAAUUGGUAGACAUUUCAAACUGUCACAUUAGGGAUACAAAAAUGAACAGGCUGGGAGUGGUGGCUCAGCCUACAAUCCCAACACUUUGGGAGGCUGAGGAAGGGGCAUCACUUGAACCAGGAGUUCAGUACUAACCUGGGCAACAAAGAGGCCCCUGUCUCUGAUAAAAAGAAAAAAAAUGAAAAAAUAAAAAUGAACAGGUAUAAAAAGAGAA